CUCCCUCUCCCCGAGUGCUAGCCCGGGCGGCCGCCGAGCUUGGCGCUCUCUCGCCUCGCUGCCUCCUCCCCCGCGCCGCGGACCCUCUCCCCUCCCUUGCGUUGCCCCCCUCUCCCGCCGCCUCCUCCCGCUCUCCUCUCGCUCUCCUCCCGCCUCCUUCUUCCAGGCGCGGCCAGCGGGGGCAAGAGCGAGGUGGCUGCGAGGAGGCGUCACUGAAAGCCCUGACUUGGGGAAGGCUGCGGGCUCGGAGCCGGAGACGCCGAGCUGGGGCCGGGUGAGUUGGGAAUCAGACUCUUGAGUUGACAGCUGGCCUAUGGUUUCUGCAUUUUGUUAAGAAGCACCUCAUGCAAGCGAGGGACCUGGGACUGCUCACAGCCAGGUGGCAUUUUUCUGAAGUUGUUCAUUAAGACUUCCCAGCAUUCCUACAGAUAUAAAUAGACAUUCUGUCCAAUAUGAGAAUAAAUACAGAAGUAUGGCUGGGCACGGUGACUGACGCCUGUAAUCCCAGCACUUUGGGAGGCUGAGAUGGGCAGAUCACUUGAGAUGAGGAGUUCCAGACCAGCCUGGCCAACAUGGCAAAACCUCGUGUCUACCAAAAAUACAAAAAUUAGCCGAGCCUGGUGGUGGGAACCUGUAAUCCCAGCCAUUCAGGGGGCUGAGGCAAGAGAAUUUCUUGAACCCGGGAGGCGGAGAUUGCAGUGAGCCGAGAUCAUGCCACUGCACUCCAGCUUGGGCAACAGAGUGAGAAUCCAUCUCAAAAUAAAUAAAUAAAUAAAUAAAAAUAAAUAAAACAGAAGUAAAGAGGAUCCUUUUUCAGUCUUGUGUUCAGCAUCCAGUGUCUCCCUGUGCCUUCACUGCAUUCCGGCGCUCUCCCUCUCCAUGCAUAGGGACUAUUUUGGAGUUUGGGCCCUGAAUUGAGACUGCUCUUGACUGUUCUUGGUCUUGUGAGAGCUCUCUUCAUAACGGCCUGAAUCCUUGGUUUGAGUUUGCCCUCCUCUCAUGAAUCUUCACCCACUAUUGGGAUCAUCAUGUUCUCAUGACUAGAGUAUUAGUUCAAUGUCUUCCGUGCCAUGGCUGUUGAAAGUGGAGAACCUGGUUGUGAAGAUGGAUGAGCCUUUUCUUUUCAAAGGAGUAGAAAAUUGUAUGGGAGGCUCCAGAUUGGUGGCCAACAGGCAGGUAAGAAGUAGCGUGGUUUGCUAGUGGUCCAGUAGCCUGUGUGCAAGCUUGGCCUCCUGAUCCACUAUGGGUUAUAUUAUUUAUUGUUAUUGAAUUUCAAACGUGGAAUUUAUUCAGAGUGAAUUGUAACAUUUGUUCUGUAGGAAUCAAGACUUCUGUCAAUGCUCAGAAAUACUGUACCUGAAGAAAACAACCCCCAGUUUUUUGCAUAUAACUUCUAGGAAAGUUUUUCAAGGAUCAAGAUGAUUUUGAGUGGAAGUUUCUUAAUGUCUAAUUACUGGAGAGCUGCACUGUGGUGACCUUUAGAGUCAUAACCCCCACUCAGGAAUUACCAUAUUGUGUGCUACUUCCACAUAUUGGAAGGUAUUUUAGACAUGGAUGCAACAUUUAUGGGACAUGUAUUAAGGCAGCAAGACAAAAUAUAUUCAACUGGAACUGUUCUAAAAAUCCAGAACUCAUGACCAGACUUUCCAAAAUCGUGUUACAGGAAAGUGGUCUUCCUCCGCCUCUAUAAACUUACUCCUGAUGAAAGAAAAUCGAGCAGAAUUUAUUGUUAUUGGAGGGCUACUCAGAGUCUUCAGCAUGCCAAUGUGUGUUGUGGCUCUUCAAGGGGAUACAGGACUCAGUGUCUGUCCUGGGAUUGCUUUGAUCUCAGAGUACCUAUGGCCCUGCCCCAGAACUCCUAUAACUCUGACCCAGUUGGGGAGAUGCUGACAUGUGGUAGGUUAAAAAUGGUUGCACAUUCUUUUUCACUCUGCCAUUAAUAACUGGAGUCUUAUUUCCCUGCCCCUUGGGUCUGGGCUGGCCUUCUGACUUCCCUUCAUGGCUGAAAUGUGGCAGAAGUAUUGUGUAAGUUCUAGAGUCUCAGCCUCAAAGGGUCUGACUACUUCCACUUUCACCUUCUUGGAACUCUGCUCUGAGACCUCUGUGUAAGUAAGCCAGUCUCGCCCCAGAAGGAUAAGGGGCCUGCAGAGGAGAGCCAAGGUUCCCCUGUUGGCAGGCAGCAUUCAUGACCAGACACGUGAAGGAAGCCUUUGUGGGCCUUCCUGCGCAGCUGACUAGCUGAAAGCCAUCGUGAGCCAGCCCAGGAGAAACCAGCAGAGGAACAGCCAGCCGAACCCUGGGAUUGUGAGAAAUAAUCAGGUGAGGCCGCAGGCGGUGCUCUGGGUCCGGGAGCGCUGUCCCCAGCAUGAACGCGGCCGGCGGCGGGAGUGAAUGACUGCAGCUGCGACUUCCUUCCCGGGCCGCCCGAGCCUCCUUCCCCACCGACUUUCUUGUUUUGAUUAACUCCGUGGACUCCUGACUCUUUCUUCGCCCGGAACAUCAAUAUGUGUCAUGUCAUUGUCACCUGUCGCUCGAUGCUCUGGACCUUGCUGAGUAUUGUGGUGGCUUUUGCCGAGCUCAUUGCCUUCAUGAGUGCAGACUGGCUGAUCGGGAAAGCGAGGAGCCGCGGCGGCGUGGAGCCGGCGGGCCCGGGCGGGGGCUCCCCGGAGCCCUACCACCCCACCCUGGGCAUCUACGCCCGCUGCAUCCGGAACCCAGGGGUGCAGCACUUCCAGCGGGACACGCUGUGCGGGCCCUACGCCGAGAGCUUCGGCGAGAUCGCCAGCGGCUUCUGGCAGGCCACAGCUAUUUUCCUGGCUGUGGGAAUCUUUAUUCUCUGCAUGGUGGCCUUGGUGUCCGUCUUCACCAUGUGUGUACAGAGCAUCAUGAAGAAAAGCAUCUUCAAUGUCUGUGGGCUGUUGCAAGGAAUUGCAGGUCUAUUCCUUAUCCUCGGUUUGAUACUCUACCCUGCUGGCUGGGGUUGCCAGAAGGCCAUAGACUACUGUGGACAUUAUGCAUCUGCCUACAAACCUGGAGACUGCUCCUUGGGCUGGGCCUUUUAUACCGCCAUUGGGGGCACAGUCCUCACUUUCAUCUGUGCUGUCUUCUCUGCACAAGCAGAAAUUGCAACCUCUAGUGACAAAGUACAGGAAGAAAUUGAAGAGGGGAAAAAUCUGAUCUGCCUCCUUUAGUUUGGAAGAGACAAUGCCAUUUUCUCCCUUGAGUAAUCUUGUGAAACAGUCCACAGUUUCAUCAUUUGAGUCAAGUGGAGAACUAACCUUUACCUACCAAAGCCACGUUCCACGGCCCGAGGCUUAAACAGGACCAAUGAGAGGCCACAUCCAGCUACGCAAAGUUACUGGACAUGCGGUCUGCAGUGCACAUUAUAAGGAAUGGAACAUGAAAAUAGUAUAUAAUCCUAGACCUGGAGUUGCCAAGUUCUGUCAGACUCCAUCUCCCCCAGGUUCAAUGAAGGAUAAUAAUCUAAAUCAUUAGGGCAGCAGUUUCUCUGGUAACGGAAGAGACCGUCCGCCAGAUCUGCAGGCUGUUUCUGCUCCAACACUGCUUGCUUGUGAGCAUCUCUGCCUCAGAAUGGGGUUUUGGGUUGGAGUUCUUGUUUUCCUCUGUUCUUUCAAGUUGUCUCCAACGAACAGAAAACUAUAAACUUACUGGGGACAGGAUGUGUGCUAAAGGGCACAGCAAGACACUGUCUUUUGCUUAGCUGACCAAAGGGGUCAGCAGGGAUGGCGUGGAGUCAUGCUGUGGAACUUAUUCUAGGCUGAAUCCUAGGGUAAGGUGGAUCAACUGAACUGUCACUCCAGAGAUUUUAGAAAUUUGAGUAAAGAAACAAUAAGGACCUAUACAAUCAUAUGAGAACAAAAAUAUGAAAUCUUGCUAGUGAAGACGUAUUUUUUCUUCUUCCCAGCAGCCAGGCUAGCACCAGUUCUGGCCCAGUCUCCUCUUCUUCUGGAGAUCACAUGUUUUUCUUCUAAGGUUAGGAUUGUGCUUUGACUGCGAAAGGAAACCUCACUGUUUCCUCCUUCCAGGGACUGAGGUCUCCAAGCUAGCUGUGGCUUAUGCAGAUGUUCACUGGGAGGACCUGCCAGAAUCUCGGCACUUGGGGGGAGACCUUUACUCCCAGUUUGGUGACCAUGCUGUAGUCAGCUCUAUUUCCAAUCCCGACAGUAGCAGAAUGGCAUUCUACAACAAAAAGAAGCUAGUUAUGGGAGUUAAGUUUUUGUAGUUACUGGUGUUGAUCCUGAAAGCAGACUGAGAUAACAUUAAAUUGCUGCAACUGAAGAACUGCAGCCAAGACCUUAAUUCCAGGAAAGCACAGAGGACAAAGUUAAUUCAAAAAGAGGCGCUAGAUCAAGGUCACAGCACUGCCUACACCUGUUUACAAAAAGAAUCAAAUACCACUAUGAAUAAGGAUUCAGGGGUUUUUAAUCUACUUUCCAUAAAUUACCAAUAUCACUGAUUCAGGAAGAUAGUAUCUCAGAAUGACCAGAGCAGCACAGAAACAAGCUACUCUGACAUUAUGGGAGCUUCAAAAUUGUAUCAUGAUACAGAAACACUCCUUAGCACUUUAAGAAAGUGAGAUGGAACUGCCAGAUUUCUGGAAGGAGAAAAAGUGUAGGUAUUUGGGUUCAUUAAUCUGCUCACUUGAGGACUUUGUUUUGAAAAAGUACCUUCUGUGGACAAGGUAUUGUGCUACCAGCUAUACAACCCUGACUUCAGAGUUUGCAACCUUGCCCUGAGUGAAUCAUGUUAAAGCUGUCUGAGUCUAAAGCACCGUAUCUUGGUGCAGAACAGAUAAUUAUACAGAGAUGGAAUGGGACAACCGCAGUUUUACUACAUUCUGGUGUUUGGCCUAUAUGAGAAACCAUCUUCUCACAGAUUAAGGGCUAAGGGCAAAAGGGGUGGGAGGUGUGGAACUAGCCUUAAUGAGUUUCCCAUUCCUGAACCAAAAUUCAAAGUGAGUGAGAUGUAAAUCCUGUGAUUUUGGUGAAGAAAAAAACGGGUAUCUUCAUAGCAGCCUAGGAAACCUUAACCAUAUCUCUAACACCACACAGAAAGAGGCUGGAGGAGCCACUGGACAAAGCUUCUGUCUCUGUGUGUACAUUUAUAAUGUUCUAACCAAGUCUCAAACCUUGAUGAAAAACACAAAAUUUUUCCAUAAACUUAUCAGAAGACUCACUUUUCUUUCUUUCUUGGAUAGAGAAACCAUUUUCUGACACUAGGUUUACAAUCUCAGUGUCCUUACAAGUUAAGUCCUAAGCUCACAGGAUCCUCCGAGCAUGUCCAUCACCUGCUCUUUGGCUAAGGUGGCAGUGUACCUCUAGAUCAACCUGGGAACAGUCACAAGGGAGUGUGACUUCUUGGCCAUAAUAAACUCACUCGAUAGUGUUUAUGUUAUUAAUCUGAAUGCAACAGAAGACAAAAGCACAGGCAUGCACACACACAGAACCCCAAACCACUAAAAACUACCUAAACACUGACUUAGUAAAUAGUAAAAAGGUAAUGUUGGGACUUUUAAACCUUGAAUCCAUUAGCCAGGCUUGGGAUGAAAGGACCAUCUAAAAUCAUGCUAGUCUAAACCAUGCUCUUCCACACAGCUGUUUAAAAACCACUGGGUAUGAGGAAUAUGCUAGAAAGAAAUGUUAAAAAUAGAUUGUUGGCUCACACUUAUUUUUCUAAUAAAUAGGACCAUUAUUACUACCAGGAAAGUCUUAUUUAUUUUGCCUGAAAUUGGCUUAAAGAAAGUCUCAUGACGGGAUGGGAUGGGCUGCGCUUCUCAAUGAACUCUGAGGCAGAAAUAUUUGCCUUGGAUUCUGUGGAUUCUUUAAACCUGUGUGCUAAUAAUUCAAACAAUGUUGCAUUAAUUGUAUAAGGGUUUUUGUAUAGUUUUCAAACAUCUGUGGUGUAAUGAUCUUUGUUAAACAUAUAUUCUGUAAAGUGCCAUAGUCUUUUUUUAUGUGUAGCAUAUUUAAAAAUAUAUAUGUAUAUUAUACAUACACAAGUUUGUGUGAAAGAUGUGCAAUAACAAAGGUGUAUGUAUGUUUUGUUGUUUUGUUUUGGAAACUGGACAGGAGUCAAAACAGGGAUGUUUGUUUCUGUUUUGGCAAGGAGAGUUCCACAUUUUUGCCUUCAUGGCUUAUUCAGUAACCCAUAAUUUUAAUGCUACACAAAUCUUAUGUGAAGAAAAGACUGGUAUGAAAUCAUUUUUUCCUGGGUCUAAAAUAAUCGCUAGUGUUAUGUCAAAGUUAAGCCCGCACGCCAGGCCCAGUUAAUGCUAGUCUUUCAUGUGAAAUGUGAAGCUGCCAUGUUGCCUUUUCUCUUAGUAGGAUAACUAGUAGCUGGUACAUAAUCACUGAGGAGCUAUUUCUUAACAUGCUUUUAUAGACCAUGCUAAUGCUAGACCAGUAUUUAAGGGCUAAUCUCACACCUCCUUAGCUGUAAGAGUCUGGCUUAGAACAGACCUCUCUGUGCAAUAACUUGUGGCCACUGGAAAUCCCUGGGCCGGCAUUUGUAUUGGGGUUGCAAUGACUCCCAAGGGCCAAAAGAGUUAAAGGCACGACUGGGAUUUCUUCUGAGACUGUGGUGAAACUCCUUCCAAGGCUGAGGGGGUCAGUAGGUGCUCUGGAGGGACUCGGCACCACUUGAUAUUCAACAGCCACUUGAGCCAAAUAUAAAAUUGUAUUUACAGCUGAUGGACUCAAUUUGAGCCUUCAAACUUGUAGUUAUCCUAUUAUAUUGUAAACUAAUACAUUGUCUAGCAUUGAUUUGGUUCCUGUGCAUAUGUAUUUUCACUAUGUGCUCCCCUCCCCAGAUCUUAAUUAAACCAGAUUUUGCAAUUCA